CUUUCUAGCCGCUGUCCCAAGGGUUGGUCUCGCGCUUUCGGCUGCGAGCUCUCUGUGGUGCUGGCAGCGACAUGUGGCGCCUCCCGGGACUCCUGGGCCGAGCUCUUCCCCGUACACUGGGACCUAGCCUCUGGAGGGUGACUCCUAAGUCCACCAGCCCAGAUGGGCCUCAGACUACCUCCUCCACUUUGCUGGUUCCUGUGCCUAACCUCGACAGGUCAGGUCCCCAUGGCCCAGGCACGAGCGGGGGUCCAAGGUCCCAUGGAUGGAAGGAUGCCUUCCAAUGGAUGUCUUCCCGUGUCUCCCCGAACACCCUAUGGGAUGCCAUAUCUUGGGGCACUCUGGCCGUGCUGGCCCUGCAGCUGGCAAGGCAGAUCCACUUCCAGGCAUCCCUGCCAGCAGGACCUCAGCGGGUAGAACACUGCUCCUGGCACAGUCCCCUGGACCGUUUCUUCUCAUCUCCCUUGUGGCACCCAUGCUCCUCACUGCGACAACACAUCCUCCCCAGCCCCGAUGGCCCAGCUCCCAGGCACACUGGCCUCAGGGAACCCAGGCUUGGCCAGGAAGAAGCCUCAGCUCAGCCCCGGAACUUCUCACACAACUCUUUGAGAGGAGCUCGUCCUCAGGACCCCUCUGAGGAAGGUCCCGGUGAUUUUGGCUUCCUGCAUGCCAGUAGUAGCAUCGAGUCCGAGGCAAAACCAGCCCAGCCUCAGCCCACUGGUGAAAAGGAACAAGAUAAAUCAAAAACUCUUUCCCUUGAGGAGGCUGUGACUUCCAUUCAGCAGCUCUUCCAGCUCAGUGUUUCCAUCGCUUUCAACUUCCUGGGAACAGAGAACAUGAAGAGUGGCGACCACACGGCAGCCUUUUCUUACUUCCAGAAAGCUGCAGCCCGCGGCUACAGCAAAGCGCAGUACAAUGCGGGCUUGUGUCAUGAGCAUGGCAGAGGCACCCCCAGGGACAUUAGCAAGGCGGUCCUUUAUUAUCAGUUGGCUGCCAGCCAGGGCCACAGCCUGGCUCAGUACCGCUAUGCCAGGUGCCUACUACGAGACCCAGCCUCUUCGUGGAACCCUGAGCGGCAGAGGGCAGUGUCCUUGCUGAAGCAGGCUGCAGACUCAGGCUUGAGAGAGGCCCAAGCUUUCCUCGGGGUGCUUUUCACCAAGGAGCCCUACCUGGAUGAGCAGAGAGCUGUGAAAUAUCUUUGGCUUGCAGCCAACAAUGGGGACUCACAGAGCAGGUACCACCUUGGAAUUUGCUAUGAGAAAGGCCUUGGUGUGCAGAGGAAUCUGGGAGAGGCCUUGAGAUGUUACCAGCAGUCAGCCGCUCUGGGAAAUGAGGCCGCCCAGGAGAGGCUGCGAGCCCUCUUUUCCAUGGGGGCUGCAGCCCCGGGGCCCAGCGACCUGACAGUUACAGGACUGAAGUCUUUCUCCAGCCCCUCCCUCUGCAGCUUGAACACCCUGCUAGCAGGAACCUCACGCCUACCACAUGCCUCGAGCACAGGCAACCUUGGCCUCCUCUGCAGAAGUGGGCAUCUCGGAGCCAGCCUGGAAGCCUCCAGCAGGGCUAUUCCCCCACACCCCUACCCACUGGAAAGGAGUGUUGUAAGACUAGGUUUUGGCUAAGGUGAGAUAAAACAUAGUCCCUGGUGCCUCUUAGGGGCCAGAGCGGGCAGGAGGUUGGAUAACAAAAAUAGAGCAUCAGCAACCCUUUCCAGGUAGAAAUUCCAGCGGGAGUUCAGGUUCCCAAGCAAUUUCACGUACAUGGCUGGUAAGUGACUGAUCUUUCCCCCCGCUUGGUAGCCUCACAGAUGAGUCUUGGAUGCAUUCACAGUCAUUUCUGGUCUGUGCACCAAAGGAUGCAUUCAGUGACCUAUGAAAAACCCUACUGAAGGGUCCAGAGACCCUGGUGCUCACCUUAGCCUUUGUCUUUGAGCAAAUAACUUACCUUCUUCCUUCUUAUGCCUGGGUUUUCUCACACUUAAAUCUGUACUACUGUUUGCCAAUGUCUGAUGUGUGUAUCCCUGGUUCACAAGAAGAUUUUAGAUGGUAUUCAAAUUAAUAUUUUCUAUUUAGUUAUAUAUUUAAUGUAUAAUAUAAAAAUAUGAUUAGCAUAUUGACCUGUAGUUUGAUAGAUGUUCUGUCUAGGAUAAAGCUAACUGUAAAAAAAAAUAGUGAAUCAGUUUAAAGAAAAACAUAACGUAAAAGUGGGCACAGAUCCAGAGAGGUAGCAAAAAUCACAGGGGUGGUUCCAUGAAUGGCUGACACUUAGGAAACUCUGAAUUAGGCCAUCCUCGAGACUAGCCCACCAUUCACCUCUGUUCAUCCCCCGUGGGCUCAUAAUCGUUUUCAUUUCACCUUUGAUUUGGAAGGAAGAAGUUUCUUGCCCAAAUGCCUGGAUGUGUCUGCUUGACUUUCAGAACUUCUCACCUCAGCCCUAAAGAGGGAGCCUGUGGGUUCUCAGAGAGAUAUCACAAUUUGAGUCCCAAAGAAGAGGCCAGAUACCCACCCACCUUCCCCCAAAUCUUAAGCACCUGCGCCAGUACAGUCAAGAAGAGGAAAGUGUGUGAAGACCCAGGUCUGGCUCUGCCACUUGCCUGGCCAUGUCACCUUGAAGCUGUGACCUGACUCCCUAUAUUGUUUCCUCAGUUGUAGACCAAAGGCAAUGGUGUCUGCCCUCCUACCUUAGAAGACAAAUGCAAGGGCAUUUCACCACAGAGAGGACCUUUGUGCUCACUUUGGCCCAGGAGGCAGUGAUGCUCAUGGUUGCAUGACUUUAUGAGUCGCUGGGCCAGGGUGAGGACCUGGGCCUCCUGACUCCUGGCCCAGAGUUCUUGUCCAUCAGUUCAUACUGCAAUUUUAUGUGAAAGCAUUAUGACUGUCCUACCCAUGGGAGAGUAAAUGUAGAUUGAAUGCUAGGAGUCUUAAAGCUGGAGAGUAUAGAUUUUGAGGUCCCCAUUUGGGAAACAUGUGCCAGAAAUGUCUAGGUGUUUAAUAAAACAGAUAUUGGAUUAUCUCAUCACUCUUGCCCUUGAGUAUUAUGGGAAGAGCCAGGGAGACGGGCAGGGGGAGCUGAAAGCUGAGGCUCCGUCCUCAUCUCUAAACUCUCCACUAACCAAUUUAAAGGAUCUUAAAAGCUUCUCCAGGAGAGAGACUUAGGAAAAAAAAAGAUUUCUGAGUCAGUGCUAAUGAGUCCAGUUACUGAAUUUGUGAAUAGCUAUUCCCUGGCUUCUGGAUGUUAGCCCAAGUUGAAUAGCAUAGAUGUGGUUGAGAGUGGGGUCUGGGAGGGAUAGAGAGCCCACCGCCCACCCCCCACAAUCCCAUGACUGAGUGGAGACCAACCAGCCUGGCCAAUUCAAAGGCAAGAAGAUUUGAGGGGGGAAAGUUGUCCACGUUUCCCUCUCUGCUUCCCACCCCAUCUCUCUCAACUUCUUAGUGGUCCUGCCAUACUUUCCUAGCACCUCUCUUUCACCCGGGGAGCCCAAGCGUCCUCUAGCUCCAUCUCCUCGCCUGCUCCCUGCCUCCUUUUCAGGGCUGCCCUGCACACUGGCUCACCACUGUUGGACCCUGCACAUGGCCACCUUCCACAGAUGGCACUCCUUGGGAGCAGGGUCCUUGUCUUUGUAUUCCAGUGUCCCCAGCACUGAGUGCAAGGCCCCAUGCAGGGUAGGAAACCUGAGGUUUCAAGCUCAGGGUUUUAAGCUGUGCAGUGCACUAAGCUCUCUGCCAAAAAACAAACAAAAAAAGGUUUCUGUGGUUAAAUAAGUUUGGGAAAUGCUGCACCAGACGUCCCCUUUUUAUAGAUUCACAAUACACAUCAGCAUAUUUGAGGUUCCAAGAAGUCCUCCAGUAAAGAACUUGGUUAACCCAAUGUUUUCUCUCACUGAAUUGAGCCCAGAGCCCGUUUCCCUACAGAUUGCUUUUGAGCCUUCCUGGGGCACCCUCUGCGUGAAAUGUCACCGUGUGCCCUCCCUGUGGAGCCCCACUCCCCAGCCUCCUCCCCUCUGUGGUCAUUUUGGAUUUUCUGACUACUUCCUUCUAGCCAUAGCUGGGGCCGAGGGCUGGUUCACAGUCUGGCCACUGGGCGUCCUGUGGUGAAGGCCAGAUGCAGCCCUCCCUGAGUGGCUCUCCCUCCCACUCAGUCACUACUGAGCUAAGUACUGAUUCAAUUUGGGGUGCCAAAGGUUGGGGGUAGGAUAUUUUUAAGCUCUCCAAUUUAAAAAGGAAGGGCCUCUCCUGUGGAAAGGGAAGGAUGGCAGAGUCGUGAGAAAGGUGUUGUCAAGGGACCAAAAAUCCUUGGCUGUUCAGUCACUGCGGUCUUGAUCCAGCCCCAGGGGGAUGGGCUUCACUGGCAGAGCUGGGUACUGCUGUGCUUUUGCCAUUAAAAUUCUGUUAUUAAUGACUCAUCAUCAGUGCCCCAGAGGAAGUGUGAGAGGACGAGAGGGAGGUGGCUCCCAUCAGCAGGGCCAGCCUGGGUCAGGAUGCUGGGUUAAAGCCCGGCGCCCUCACCAAUGAGACCUUUGUGGGAAGCUCUACUGCCUCAGUUUCCCUAUCCGGAGAUGCUGUUUUCAGGGAGUCCUGACACUAUGAUGGGAACAAGGCUAUUUGGUUUACUAUAUCAUUAGUGCUAAUAUAGUGUGGGGCACUCAGAUGUUCAGUAAAUAUACAUUCAACAAAUAAGUGAGUGAUUAUACUCAACUCCCCCCACCCAAUGCCCAGCACCAAGCCUACCCAGCACAUAGUAGGUACUUUAAGUAAUUUGAAUGAAUAAUUUUAAAUAACUUGAAUGAAUAAUUCUGUAUUGCCCCCCACUCGCCGCCUAUACACACGCACACACGCACACACACACACACGGUUUCCUGUGCUACUUCUGGCACUUAGUAAUUAUUCAAUAAACACAAAAUGUUUGUUGCA